UAUAGUCUCAUGUUUGCUAUUGGUAUUUAGUAAAUUAUUUUCUUCAUUCUUAAGUAGUUUUUUAAAUCCCUUUUUUUAAUUAAAAAUUUUGUUAAUAGUAGCUGCUUAAUUUCAUUAAAUGCCUUUUUUUCUUUUGCUAAUAUAAUUACAUAUUUUUCCUUUAAUUUUUCAUGCAAUGAAUUAUUGACAUCCUUAGUACACAGUUUUUAUAACAUGUAAUUGGACUACUCAGAUUUUGUAACUGACAUCCUGGUUUUAGGUUGUAUUUUGGAUAGAUUAGGCUGUUAGAUAAUUUCUGGAUCCAUUUAACAUCUUAUUAUAGAAAAAUGAGUUGGGGUAAGGGAGACACAAGACCAAGCACUAUCUUAAUAAUAGUUUCUUGUCAUAUUUUAGGCCACUAAAAUGGCAAUAUAAUUUUUUUUUGCCCUCUAGGGAUUUAAAUUUCAAAUUAGAGGUAGCACAAGAACAAUAAACAUACAAGGCAAAUGAGCUUAUACCUAUUUCAUCUGGAGUACAGGGAAAGGGAAUAACAGUUAAUUUUCAGAUGAAUUUUACAUUUGAGCCAAGGAAGGCCAGGGGCCAGAGAAAGAGAAGGGAAGUAAAGAGAGAACUUGCUUCUCGACCUGCUGCUCUUGUAACUAUUGUUUUUCUGAUGAGCCAGUGACAUGAUUCCUGUUUUCAGCUGUUAUCCCUGUCUGGGCUCUAUAGUUAACACAUGUACACAACAAACACAUUUGUCACUAUGAAAGGACAACAACGAAUGGCCAUGAGUCAGUCUGUGGCGGGAGGUGUGGGGAGAAAGGCCUUGAUAGGCUGGGGUCUUAAUUUGCCAUUUCCCUUGUUUUGAGAAGUCAGUGAAAUUUGAUCAGUGAGGUUAGGGCAGAGGGCUGCUGGCCCUAGGAGCCUGCACAGAAUUCCCAGGAUGUGGGGACAGUCCUCCCCGCCAGAGAGAAAUAAGAAAAAUCCAAACAGACACCCUGUAGGCUGGCAGAGUAGUGCAUAGAUUGCCCAAAUAAAAGGCUUUGGGGUUUGUGGAAAGGUUGAGAGGAUAUUGUGGUGAGUAAAUGUAACAUGACACAGUCAAGUAAGAGUGAAGAGACAAUGGUUUCCAGAUCCUUAAAAAACACCUUCUGAAGGGGUUAAAAGAGUUUCGAAUGCCGAUAGUGCUGCCGUAGGAUCACUCUGGGCCCUGCGACAGCCUAUUAGGGGCCCAUGCACAUGAUUGGUGCUCAGUGAGUAUUAGCUGGAUGAAGGGAUGCAUGACUCAGUGAUGAACUCUGUUAAGGUGAAGUCCAAAACAGCUCUGCCAAGUCUGUGUUCCAUAGUACCCUAAAGGUGAAGAUAAAUGUGGGUGAAAGGAGGUGAAGUCAAAAAUUAUAGACAGGAAUUGGGGGAAUGCAGCAUUGGUCGUCAAUGGAGGAGCUCUUUCCUGUGUCUAGGAGCGUGGAGAUGUUGGCUCUUUCCCAGUGCUUUUUACAUUUCCCCCAGAGCAGCAGUUCCGGAUGUUAGAAAGGUAGGCAGCUGAUUCGUAGAUUCCAGGUUUAAUGAAGAAUGUGAUUCUUUCACACUAAAUCAUGGUUUGGCCUAACUAUUCAAAUCACUCUAGGGAAGGACAUGCACAGAAGGUCAGGGGUGAAAGCGGUACCUGUCACCCCUUACACGUUAACUCACUUACUUUUUUCCUUAAGUUCACAAUGACAUACAACAUAAUAAUAGAAACAAUAUUAAAACCAGUCUAUGACCCUCACUGGUUUUGGGAAUUGAUGUGUUAAUACUUUAUCUCUACUUAAUGCUUAUCCAUUCUUACCAAUUCCAGGACAUUACUUGAAAUGUAAAAAAAUUGGAAACCCCAAAUUUCCAUAUGUCUACUGUGGCUGAUAUUUAUUGCUAUAUCUUUAUUACUUUUCUGCUAUCUGUCCUAAGAAAAUGCAUUUCCUAUUUCACUGAUUUUUGAGAGCUUCUGUUCCAUUUGGAACCGCAGAAGCAGCAUUAAGGGCAUAAAAUUUGUUGGGAAAUGGUGCUUCUUGAAGAUAAAGAGACCAAGAAGGAGAUAAAACUGCUUGAUAAAGACUUUUAAUGCAGCCAAUCAGACAGGCAUCAGCUAUUUCAUGAUUAUGUUUAUUUUCAAGAUGGAGAAUAUAUACUUCUAGAAAGAUAUCCUACCAUUUUCCUUUGGCAGAUAGAAGUAGACAUAACUAUUAUUAACAGGAUUGUCCUACAAGUGCAACAUUGACAAAACAUAAAAUGGGAAUAUGAAUCCAGCUUAAAUAAUGGCUGCUUUAGUAAGUAACAUUCAAAUAGGACUUUUUGUUUUAUAUUUAUAAUGCAAACUAGUAGUGUGUUUAAUUGUAGGUUAGAAAGGUAAAUGUGGGUCAAGGCCAGCUAUUAUAGAUUUUAUUUUUCCUGAGAAAGGAAGUCUCUGCCAAGAUAUGAUAAAAUAUACACACUGGUUCCCUGUAAUUUGGUAACAGAUAAUUUCCCAGGCUUCCGAUCUAUACUACUUUCAACCACUUUUAAAGCUGUGCUUUUUACCAAGUUGAAAUAAUGAAGAUAGUUUAAAACUUAACAUUUGGGUUUGUUUUCAAAUCCUUUUAGGAGACAGAAAAUGAUAUUAUUUAUCUUUACCUUUUUCCUUUUGGAACUGACUUGCAAGAAAAUCUAACAGACAGGUUGAAAAGUUGUCCUGACAGCCUUCAGUAGGAGCCAUAAUGAGACCACAUUAUUGUACUUAAGCAUUUAUUUCCUUAAAGUUUACAUCUUUAAGGAAGAAACUAAAUGACUUAGCUUAUUGAAGCUUCUUAGAGGUUAAAAAUAAAGAGCACCUUUUAAAAAUACACUCUGGUCCAAAAAUAGGUGUACCCAUGUAUAACUUUUAGGCACACGUUUUAUUUUAUGCUGAGUAUUAGGUCAAUUACUCCAUAACUUUUCUAAUGGUUUGUUGAGCAGUUGAAGGUUUUACCUGUUAACAAAUACACCUGAAGAUGUCUAGAAUCUGUGAAACUAAAUUUACAUGAGAUUCUUUUCCUUGUCUCCAUCACAUUAAAUAUAUGCUAGAGCCAGAGGUAACCAGAAAAGCAUCGAAAGGGCUGGUCCAAGUGGCUCAUUCCUAUAAUCCCAACAUUUUGGGAGGCUGAGGCGGGAGCAUCACUUGAGUCUAGGAGUUUGAAACCAGCCUGGGUAACAUAGCAAGACCUCAUCUUUACAAAAAAUUUAAAAAUUAGCCUGACAUGGUGGCGAGUGCCUGUGGUCCUAGCUACUCAGGCGGCAGAGGUGGGAGGGUCAAUUGAGCCCAGGAGUUCGAGGUUACAGUGAGCUAUGAUGGCACCACUGCACUCCAGUCUGGGUGAUAGAGGCAGACCCUGUCUCAAAAAAAAGUAUCAAGAUUUGUCCUCUACACUAAAAUAGAAUUCCUCCCACCCUGGUAUUGUUACUUGUUGCACCCUAUCAUUAAAAAUAUGCAAAGUUUUGUGGAAACACUAUUUCUUUGAAGUAUGUUUCUUUUCUGCUUCUUUUAAGUGUGCUUGAAUUUGUUAUUAUGCCUUACUGCUCACAUGAUACAGAUCUAAAAAAUGCAAGGCUGACCUACAUUUCUGACUCUGGUUCUGGCCUGACUUGAGAGCCACAUGGGAAGUGGCUGCCGAGACAAAGUGUACCCUUCUUGCGGCAAGUGCUCGGCUGGGCAAAGCCCUGUCUCCUUCCCUUGGCAGAAAGCUCCCCUUCUGCUGCAGAGAGCCAGUCACCUGGCCUAGUCAAAAAGAAACUUGGCUAGUCUAAGAACUAUUUGUGCUUUCCAUGGAGCAAUGAGCGAUCAUUUUCUCUUUUCUAUCUCGAUUCCCUCUAGCAACUCAGCUCCCACCUCAUUCGUCUUACCUAGAGCAUAUCCUUUCUCUUGGACAGAGCUCCAAUGCCACUUUUAAAAAGAUAAUGAAGUGAAUUUUUGAGGGCUGAUCUUUACUCCUUGCCAUUUGGCAGCCCUUCUUCCCAACAGAGGGCAAUACCCCACUAGCCAAACAUUUCGUGUUAGAAAACUCCAAGCCUUCCUACUGGCAGGCACUUCCCAUGUUGGAAUCGAGGACGUCUGAUUUUGGUAGCUCAGAGUUUCCCAGAUCUAAAGAGGACUUGGCUUAUUAGUUAAAGAACUUUCUAACUGAGGAGGAAUGAUUACCAUUCAGCUUUAAGUGCCAGGAUGAGUGUCCUGUUGGGACCUAUGGCGUUCUCUGUGCUGAGACCUGCCAGUGUGUCAACGGAGGGAAGUGUUACCACGUGAGCGGCGCAUGCCUCUGUGAAGCAGGCUUUGCUGGCGAGCGCUGCGAAGCACGCCUGUGUCCUGAGGGGCUCUACGGCAUCAAAUGUGACAAACGGUGUCCCUGCCACCUGGAAAACACUCAUAGCUGUCACCCCAUGUCUGGAGAGUGUGCCUGCAAGCCGGGCUGGUCAGGACUCUACUGUAAUGAGACAUGUUCUCCUGGAUUCUACGGGGAAGCUUGCCAGCAGAUCUGCAGCUGCCAAAAUGGGGCAGACUGUGACAGUGUGACUGGAAAGUGCACCUGUGCCCCAGGAUUCAAAGGAAUUGACUGCUCUACCCCAUGCCCUCUGGGAACCUAUGGGAUAAACUGUUCCUCUCGCUGUGGCUGUAAAAAUGAUGCAGUCUGCUCUCCUGUGGACGGGUCUUGUACUUGCAAGGCAGGCUGGCACGGGGUGGACUGCUCCAUCAGAUGUCCCAGUGGCACAUGGGGCUUUGGCUGUAACUUAACAUGCCAGUGCCUCAACGGGGGAGCCUGCAACACCCUGGACGGGACCUGCACGUGUGCACCUGGAUGGCGCGGGGAGAAAUGCGAACUUCCCUGCCAGGAUGGCACGUACGGGCUGAACUGUGCUGAGCGCUGCGACUGCAGCCACGCAGAUGGCUGCCACCCUACCACGGGCCAUUGCCGCUGCCUCCCCGGAUGGUCAGGUGUCCACUGUGACAGCGUGUGUGCUGAGGGACGCUGGGGCCCCAACUGCUCCCUGCCCUGCUACUGUAAAAAUGGGGCUUCAUGCUCCCCUGAUGAUGGCAUCUGCGAGUGUGCACCAGGCUUCCGAGGCACCACUUGUCAGAGGAUCUGCUCCCCUGGUUUUUAUGGGCAUCGCUGCAGCCAGACAUGCCCACAGUGCGUUCACAGCAGCGGGCCCUGCCACCACAUCACCGGCCUGUGUGACUGCUUGCCUGGCUUCACAGGCGCCCUCUGCAAUGAAGUGUGUCCCAGUGGCAGAUUUGGGAAAAACUGUGCAGGAAUUUGUACCUGCACCAACAACGGAACCUGUAACCCCAUUGACAGAUCUUGUCAGUGUUACCCCGGUUGGAUUGGCAGUGACUGCUCUCAACCAUGUCCACCUGCCCACUGGGGCCCAAACUGCAUCCACACGUGCAACUGCCAUAAUGGAGCUUUCUGCAGCGCCUACGAUGGGGAAUGUAAAUGCACUCCUGGCUGGACAGGGCUCUACUGCACUCAGAGAUGUCCUCUAGGGUUUUAUGGAAAAGAUUGUGCACUGAUAUGCCAAUGUCAAAACGGAGCUGACUGCGACCACAUUUCUGGGCAGUGUACUUGCCGCACUGGAUUCAUGGGACGGCACUGUGAGCAGAAGUGCCCUUCAGGAACAUAUGGCUAUGGCUGUCGCCAGAUAUGUGAUUGUCUGAACAACUCCACCUGCGACCACAUCACUGGGACCUGUUACUGCAGCCCCGGAUGGAAGGGAGCGAGAUGUGAUCAAGCUGGUGUUAUCAUAGUUGGAAAUCUGAACAGCUUAAGCCGAACCAGUACUGCUCUCCCUGCUGAUUCCUACCAGAUCGGGGCCAUUGCAGGCAUCAUCAUUCUUGUCCUAGUUGUUCUCUUCCUACUGGCAUUGUUCAUUAUUUAUAGACACAAGCAGAAGGGAAAGGAAUCAAGCAUGCCAGCAGUUACCUACACCCCUGCUAUGAGGGUCGUCAAUGCAGAUUAUACCAUUUCAGGAACCCUUCCUCACAGCAAUGGUGGAAACGCUAAUAGCCACUACUUCACCAAUCCCAGUUACCACACGCUCACCCAGUGUGCCACAUCCCCUCACGUCAACAACAGGGACAGGAUGACUGUCACGAAGUCAAAAAACAAUCAACUGUUUGUGAAUCUUAAAAAUGUGAACCCUGGGAAGAGAGGCCCUGUGGGGGACUGCACUGGGACAUUGCCGGCUGACUGGAAACAUGGCGGCUACCUCAACGAGCUCGGUGCUUUUGGACUUGACAGAAGCUAUAUGGGAAAAUCCUUAAAAGACCUGGGAAAGAAUUCUGAAUAUAAUUCAAGUAACUGCUCCCUAAGCAGUUCUGAGAACCCAUAUGCCACUAUUAAAGACCCACCUGUACUUAUCCCGAAAAGCUCAGAGUGUGGUUAUGUGGAGAUGAAAUCGCCGGCACGAAGAGAUUCCCCAUAUGCAGAGAUCAAUAACUCAACUUCAGCCAACAGGAAUGUCUAUGAAGUUGAACCUACAGUGAGUGUUGUCCAAGGAGUAUUCAGCAAUAAUGGGCGUCUCUCCCAGGAUCCAUAUGACCUCCCAAAGAACAGUCACAUCCCUUGUCAUUAUGACCUGCUGCCAGUCCGAGACAGUUCAUCCUCCCCUAAGCAAGAGGACAGUGGUGGUAGCAGCAGCAACAGCAGCAGCAGCAGUGAAUGACACCAAAGGACCGCUUGGUAGCCACUGGAACCCUUUCCAGAACUGCUGUUUGGUUCUUCUCCAUCCUCAAUUUUGCCACUUUCAUGUGAAUGUUAGUCAAUUCGGUGGGCAAUUUUUGGACAUGAACCAGAAAGCUGAAAGCUGAGGCUGACACGGACUGUAGGUGCUUUUUGUUCAGGUGGAUUCGAAGGAGUUAGAGAUGUGAUUUCCCAUUGCUGUUAGUUUUAGAACUAUACCCGUGAAGCAUGACUUAUUGUAAGAUGUUGGCUGAAAGCAUGAACUUGCAGAACUCCCUCGGAGACGCAGGUUGCAGUGGACAUUGGGAUUGUUGCUUGAAAAAUUAAAAUUUGAAUAUUUUCUCUCUCAUUUGCAUCAUACAGCUCUACCUAGGAUUGUACAGUUUACCAUAAAAUUUACUUCAUGAAAGUGGGAAUCACUGAACAUGUAGAAGACAAGGAACAUAUUGUUAACUCCUGAUUCUUAACUUUAUUCAACUGGACUCAGAAUUGUAGGGAUAAUAUGAAUGCAGGAGGAAACAUUCUGUCAGGCGGUAUGACUGGACAGACUUUGAAUAUACUCUAAAAGUGGACAGAAAAUUUACGAAAAUCUUAGAUUUUGUUUAGAAUGAGAAAAUAUACAAUUAGAAUUAUUUUAGAAAUAGUAGGAAGUAUUGCAGAAGUCAAUACACAAAUGUGCCAGGCAGAGGUGGUUUUCUCUGUUUGACUCUCAACCAACUUCAGAUCUAUGACAUUAUUCUGAUCACUGGCUCCAUCAUACAUAUUCACCACUUGAGAUUCAUAACAUAUCAAUAGUUAUUUCAUAAAUAUAGAAAUGAAAUAAUUUUAUUUUUGACAGACUGGAUGGAAUGAGUGUGUAAUGAUUGAUAAAGGUUGUAAAUUUUAAAUGCAAGAUGACGCUUACGUUCUGUAAACCAUUAGUAAUACAUGCUGUAAUAUAGAAUUAGUGGAACAUUUUGAUUAAUCUUUCCCUAGAAGUGACUGAAAUAUUUUUGUGCAUAUUUGAGAAAGGGAACUUUCCUUUUAUUAAUUGUCAAUUUAGAGAAACUAUGCUUAAGCUGGUCUUUUGCAUUGCUAAUGUGACAUGUACCCAACUUUUCAUUAAUUUGUAUUUCCAUUUUUAAAUUGCAUAUUCUAUGUUUUGUAGUGUUUGGAUUGUUAAUGAAAAAAUAUUAUAUGUUCGUUAUUCCUUGUAUUAUUGCCACUUAUCUUUUGCUUGAUAAAAAUGCGUUGUUCUUUUUUCUUUUGGAGGGACAAGAUGAAAAUAUAUAAUUUGAAUUGAUUAAAAUUGGUCGUUACUAAAAUAGUAUAGUAACCACAAGUGAUUGGCUUAUAAAUGAAGUAGAAAUGCUUUUUAAUAUUCCAAAAUAGAGUUCCUUUUGAUCUGUUGGUGCUGAGCCUUGGUUAAACCAGGGAGAAGGGGAGCAGAAAGGAAACGUUGUUACUGAUGAGUACCACAGACUCAUCUUAAAAAAAACUCUCAUUAUGGUGAUCAUAGAAUUGACCAUCCAAACUGGGACACUCUUGAGAGUAAAUGGAGGGCAUUAUUAAUAAUUAUCUUGUAAUGAACUUAAAUCUGGACUGUUCCAGGCAAACCAGACUUAUCUUGCAAUAUGAGAAUGCUGACACAAUGCAGGAAAGCCAGUUUCCCUUUUGUUGAUCUACUUGACCAAGCAAAGGGGCUGAAAAACUGAAUAAGGAAACAACUUUAUAAGAGAAACAGUGGUCUUCAAUCUUUUAAAGACAUGAAAUCCUAUAUGGCAUUCUGUCUCAGUGAGUCAGUUAACAAAUACGUAUGUGCAACCCUUCUGCUAGUAGUGCACAUAAGUGAUUAUCCCUGCCAGGUAUCGAGUUGGAAUAUCCAGUUAUUUCAUGUCACACAUCGGCACGUAUGAUGGUGGUUUGGUCAGAUGGAUAAUACAGCAGACACACUUAGAACACUCACUGCACUGGUGGCUGUUCAUUUUGAGGAACUCCAAAGUCAAUUCAAGGAAAUAAGGAAUGACCUGGAACAGGCCUUAGAAACAAUUGAUUUAUUCCAAUAGUUAACCACUGGCUGGCUCCCAACUCUAGGUGAUAGGCAUCUAAUUGAGACAUGUGUGAGUCAAUAGCCAUCGGGGUCCUUUUUGGUGAGAAGAAAUAAGACAUUUUCUCCCUUUUAAAGAUCAUCUCUUCAGAGCUGCAUGGUAAAUUUGAAUUUCCCCAUUGUUCUCUAGAGCUAGGUCAAAAAAACAACUGUUUCUUUUCUUAUUCCACUAUUAAUAAAUUGAAAGCUUGCUGUACAAAGGCAACAGCAACUUAAAAAAGAAAAUCUGGACAAUAGAUGUGGACUCCAAGGGGCCACUGCCAUCCCUUCCUGUGUGCUCUUUUUGACAAGUAAAUCACUCCAGUUAGCUGAUGUCCUGAAAUGACAUUUGUACCUGAGGCAAUUCUUAUUAGAGCUUACUCAGGACUUUUCAAACAUCAGGACACACAUAGCAAUUUGGAUGUUGUAAAACUACGUGUUACAUUUGGAGAGGUCUUGUUGAGAAGGCAAAAUUUUCUAAAUAUUUUGAUAUCAAUUUGGGUAAAGAAAGGAAUACUUUUGUUAGAAUGAGAAUUAAAGAGAAAACAAAAGAAUCUUGGCAAAAUUUUCCCUCUGAAAUUACAAACUUUAGGAACUUUUCCAGAUGUAUCGAAUUUAAUUUGACAUUGAUGUCACUCUUCAUACCAAGUGAAUCUAUUCUCAUGAACUUUGAACCCAUGUUAAUUUUGGACCCUAUAACUAAUUUCCUUUCUGUAUCCCAUGGUGGUCAAAGCAGUAAAGGAGUUUAGAGAUACUUAGCAAAUGCCAUUCAUAUAGUAUUGUUAGCCAAACUAUUAUUCCUUCCUUAGAAGUUGAUGUAUCAGAAAAUUUAUAAGUUAUUUGUAUUUAUAUAUAAGUACAUCAGAACUUGCCCACAUGAUAACUCAUGUUUGCUUUAAUAAGGAAAAUAUGUUAUUUGAGGUUAAUUAUAUGAUAGUGAGGAACAUUUUACAAUUAUUUACAGUGUUUGACAUUAAUUGCUGUCCUAUGAUACAGUAGUAAUGUUAACAGAGAGUUUAAUAUGUUUAGCAUUAUCUUUAUGGAAUUUAUAUUCACCAAUUUCAGGAAAACCAACCAUAGAACUUUAUAAUAGGACAGUUAUAACCUGACUGAACCAAAUCCAUCAGCAUAAUGACUGUGUGUUCUGAGAAAUGCAAACAACUUUAUGAAAGUGUGGUCAUCUUGACCCCCAAAGAGCCACAGUAGCUGUCAAUUAUUGAGAUUUUUAAAUGGUAAAUAUUGCAAAAGUUAAACAAGGGUACCACAAUAUCAUUUAUAAUUGAUGUCAAUAUUAGUAGUCCACUUUAUGCUUAAAAUAAAAUCAUAAAAAAUCAAGUUUUAAGGUUAUAUUUUUUAAAAUAAUGAAUUUUCUAUCUCUAGGCAACAUGUCUUUAUUAUUCAAGCUGAAUGUUUAAGAGAGAUUUUGGUCUUAAAGGCUUCACAUCAUGAAAGUGUACAUGCAUAUGCAAGUGUGAAUUACGUGGUAUGGAUGUUUGCUUGUUUAUUAACUAAAGAUGUACAGCAAACUGCCCGUUUAGAGUCCUGUUAAUAUUGAUGUCCUAACACUGGGUCUGCUUAUGCUAGUUCAGUAUUUGGUCUAGGCUUCAUUUUGAUAUGACUGAAUUGCAAUCUAUAUUUUUAAAAAGAAAAAUCAAAAUACAUUAGGGUUUACUUGGUUGUGGCAAACAAACAAAAAAUGCUUUCAGUGUUGAAAUAUCUCUAUUUUCCAAAGAUGAUAAACUUUCAUCGUUCUUAGCCUACAUUGUCAUUUAUAUCACCAAAUGAGUUUAUAGAUUAAUGCAAUAAACUUUCUAAUAAAAAA